ACAAGGGCGGCUGGCUGGCUGGCUGGCUGGCUGUCCGGGCAGGCCUCCUGGCUGCACCUGCCGCAGUGCACAGUCCGGCUGAGGUGCACGGGAGCCCGCCGGCCUCUCUCUGCCCGCGUCCGUCCGUGAAAUUCCGGCCGGGGCUCACCGCGAUGGCCCUCCCGACACCCUCGGACAGCACCCUCCCCGCGGAAGCCCGGGGACGAGGACGGCGACGGAGACUCGUUUGGACCCCGAGCCAAAGCGAGGCCCUGCGAGCCUGCUUUGAGCGGAACCCGUACCCGGGCAUCGCCACCAGAGAACGGCUGGCCCAGGCCAUCGGCAUUCCGGAGCCCAGGGUCCAGAUUUGGUUUCAGAAUGAGAGGUCACGCCAGCUGAGGCAGCACCGGCGGGAAUCUCGGCCCUGGCCCGGGAGACGCGGCCCGCCAGAAGGCCGGCGAAAGCGGACCGCCGUCACCGGAUCCCAGACCGCCCUGCUCCUCCGAGCCUUUGAGAAGGAUCGCUUUCCAGGCAUCGCCGCCCGGGAGGAGCUGGCCAGAGAGACGGGCCUCCCGGAGUCCAGGAUUCAGAUCUGGUUUCAGAAUCGAAGGGCCAGGCACCCGGGACAGGGUGGCAGGGCGCCCGCGCAGGCAGGCGGCCUGUGCAGCGCGGCCCCCGGCGGGGGUCACCCUGCUCCCUCGUGGGUCGCCUUCGCCCACACCGGCGCGUGGGGAACGGGGCUUCCCGCACCCCACGUGCCCUGCGCGCCUGGGGCUCUCCCACAGGGGGCUUUCGUGAGCCAGGCAGCGAGGGCCGCCCCCGCGCUGCAGCCCAGCCAGGCCGCGCCGGCAGAGGGGAUCUCCCAACCUGCCCCGGCGCGCGGGGAUUUCGCCUACGCCGCCCCGGCUCCUCCGGACGGGGCGCUCUCCCACCCUCAGGCUCCUCGCUGGCCUCCGCACCCGGGCAAAAGCCGGGAGGACCGGGACCCGCAGCGCGACGGCCUGCCGGGCCCCUGCGCGGUGGCACAGCCUGGGCCCGCUCAAGCGGGGCCGCAGGGCCAAGGGGUGCUUGCGCCACCCACGUCCCAGGGGAGUCCGUGGUGGGGCUGGGGCCGGGGUCCCCAGGUCGCCGGGGCGGCGUGGGAACCCCAAGCCGGGGCAGCUCCACCUCCCCAGCCCGCGCCCCCGGACGCCUCCGCCUCCGCGCGGCAGGGGCAGAUGCAAGGCAUCCCGGCGCCCUCCCAGGCGCUCCAGGANCCGGCGCCCUGGUCUGCANUCCCCUGCGGCCUGCUGCUGGAUGAGCUCCUGGCGAGCCCGGAGUUUCUGCAGCAGGCGCAACCUCUCCUAGAAACGGAGGCCCCGGGGGAGCUGGAGGCCUCGGAAGAGGCCGCCUCGCUGGAAGCACCCCUCAGCGAGGAAGAAUACCGGGCUCUGCUGGAGGAGCUUUAGGACGCGGGGUUGGGACGGGGUCGGGUGGUUCGGGGCAGGGCCGUGGCCUCUCUUUCGCGGGGAACACCUGGCUGGCUACGGAGGGGCGUGUCUCCGCCCCGCCCCCUCCACCGGGCUGACCGGCCUGGGAUUCCUGCCUUCUAGGUCUAGGCCCGGUGAGAGACUCCACACCGCGGAGAACUGCCAUUCUUUCCUGGGCAUCCCGGGGAUCCCAGAGCCGGCCCAGGUACCAGCAGGCUGAGCCCUGCAACGCGGCGCGAGGCCGACAGCCCCGGCCACGGAGGAGCCACACGCAGGACGACGGAGGCGUGAUUUUGGUUUCCGCGUGGCUUUGCCCUCCGCAAGGCGGCCUGUUGCUCACGUCUCUCCGGCCCCCGAAAGGCUGGCCAUGCCGACUGUUUGCUCCCGGAGCUCUGCGGGCACCCGGAAACAUGCAGGGAAGGGUGCAAGCCCGGCACGGUGCCUUCGCUCUCCUUGCCAGGUUCCAAACCGGCCACACUGCAGACUCCCCACGUUGCCGCACGCGGGAAUCCAUCGUCAGGCCAUCACGCCGGGGAGGCAUCUCCUCUCUGGGGUCUCGCUCUGGUCUUCUACGUGGAAAUGAACGAGAGCCACACGCCUGCGUGUGCGAGACCGUCCCGGCAACGGCGACGCCCACAGGCAUUGCCUCCUUCACGGAGAGAGGGCCUGGCACACUCAAGACUCCCACGGAGGUUCAGUUCCACACUCCCCUCCACCCUCCCAGGCUGGUUUCUCCCUGCUGCCGACGCGUGGGAGCCCAGAGAGCGGCUUCCCGUUCCCGCGGGAUCCCUGGAGAGGUCCGGAGAGCCGGCCCCCGAAACGCGCCCCCCUCCCCCCUCCCCCCUCUCCCCGUUCCUCUUCGUCUCUCCGGCCCCACCACCACCACCGCCACCACGCCCUCCCCCCCCACCCCCCCCCCCCACCACCACCACCACCACCACCCCGCCGGCCGGCCCCAGGCCUCGACGCCCUGGGUCCCUUCCGGGGUGGGGCGGGCUGUCCCAGGGGGGCUCACCGCCAUUCAUGAAGGGGUGGAGCCUGCCUGCCUGUGGGCCUUUACAAGGGCGGCUGGCUGGCUGGCUGGCUGUCCGGGCAGGCCCCCUGGCUGCACCUGCCGCAGUGCACAGUCCGGCUGAGGUGCACGGGAGCCCGCCGGCCUCUCUCUGCCCGCGUCCGUCCGUGAAAUUCCGGCCGGGGCUCACCGCGAUGGCCCUCCCGACACCCUCGGACAGCACCCUCCCCGCGGAAGCCCGGGGACGAGGACGGCGACGGAGACUCGUUUGGACCCCGAGCCAAAGCGAGGCCCUGCGAGCCUGCAGCCUCCCAGCUGCCAGCGCGGAGCUCCUGGCGGUCAAAAGCAUACCUCUGUCUGUCUUUGCCCGCUUCCUGGCUAGACCUGCGCGCAGUGCGCACCCCGGCUGACGUGCAAGGGAGCUCGCUGGCCUCUCUGUGCCCUUGUUCUUCCGUGAAAUUCUGGCUGAAUGUCUCCCCCCACCUUCCGACGCUGUCUAGGCAAACCUGGAUUAGAGUUACAUCUCCUGGAUGAUUAGUUCAGAGAUAUAUUAAAAUGCCCCCUCCCUGUGGAUC